AGGCUUUCUGACCCGGAAUGGAGGAGGCGGAGGAGCUGCUCUUGGAGGGGAAGAAGGCGCUGCAACUCGGUGAGUGACCUGCGAUGUCCGCGACCCUCAACCUUGGCCCAGCCCGCGAGCCGCGCCUGGGCCUGGACUUAGGAUGGAACCCUUCCGGAGAAGGCUGUACGCAGGGCCUCAAAGACGUCCCACCCGAGCCGACCCGAGACAUCCUCGCUUUAAAGAGCCUUCCCCGGGGCUUGGCCCUUGGCCCCUCACUCGCCAAGGAACAGCGCUUGGGGGUCUGGUGUGUCGGGGACCCCCUGCAGCCCGGCCUGCUGUGGGGGCCGCUGGAAGAGGAGUCUGCCUCCAAGGAGAAGGGCGAGGGAGUAAAGCCACGGCAGGAGGAGAACCUGUCAUUAGGCCCAUGGGGAGACGUGUGUGCCUGUGAGCAGAGUUCUGGCUGGACUAGCUUGGUACAACGGGGCAGGCUGGAGAGUGAGGGAAAUGUGGCCCCAGUGCGGAUCAGCGAGAGGCUUCAUCUGCAAGUGUACCAGCUGGUGCUGCCAGGCUCUGAACUGCUGCUGUGGCCCCAGCCUUCCUCUGAGGGCCCAAGUCUCACCCAGCCUGGGCUGGACAAAGAGGCAGCUGUAGCAGUGGUGACAGAAGUGGAGUCUGCUGUACAGCAGGAAGUGGCCUCCCCUGGGGAGGAUGCAGCAGAACCUUGCAUAGAUCCUGGUUCCCAGUCACCCUCUGGCAUCCAGGCAGAGAAUAUGGUGAGCCCUGGACUUAAGUUCCCAACCCAGGACCGAAUUUCCAAGGAUAGCCAGCCACUUGGCCCAUUGCUUCAGGAUGGCGACGUGGAUGAGGAAUGCCCGGCCCAGGCACAGAUGCCACCUGAACUUCAGAGCAAUUCGGCUACCCAGCAGGACCCAGAUGGCAGUGGAGCCAGUUUCUCAUCUUCUGCCAGGGGCACCCAGCCGCAUGGCUACCUGGCCAAGAAGUUACACAGCCCCAGUGAUCAGUGCCCACCCAGAGCAAAGACCCCAGAGCCUGGAGCCCAGCAGUCUGGCUUCCCUACACUCUCGCGGAGCCCUCCUGGCCCAGCAGGAAGCUCCCCAAAGCAGGGGCGACGGUACCGGUGUGGAGAGUGUGGCAAGGCAUUCCUACAGCUGUGCCACCUAAAGAAGCACGCAUUUGUGCACACGGGCCACAAGCCCUUUCUUUGCACUGAGUGUGGCAAGAGCUAUAGCUCAGAGGAGAGCUUCAAAGCCCAUAUGCUGGGCCACCGUGGGGUGCGGCCCUUCCCCUGUCCACAAUGCGACAAGGCCUAUGGCACCCAGCGAGACCUCAAAGAGCACCAGGUGGUACAUUCAGGUGCCCGGCCCUUUGCUUGUGACCAGUGUGGCAAGGCCUUUGCCCGCCGGCCCUCCCUGCGGCUGCAUCGCAAGACCCACCAGGUGCCAGCUGCCCCUGCCCCUUGCCCAUGCCCUGUGUGUGGGCGGCCCCUGGCCAACCAGGGCUCCCUGCGGAACCAUAUGAGGCUCCAUACAGGAGAAAAGCCUUUCCUGUGCCCGCACUGUGGCCGGGCGUUUCGUCAGCGGGGCAACCUGCGUGGGCAUUUGCGGCUCCACACCGGGGAGCGUCCUUACCGCUGCCCACACUGUGCCGAUGCCUUCCCCCAGCUGCCUGAACUGCGGCGCCAUCUCAUCUCACACACCGGGGAGGCCCACUUGUGCCCGGUGUGUGGCAAGGCCCUCCGAGACCCACACACGCUCCGAGCUCACGAGCGCCUGCACUCCGGAGAGAGGCCCUUUCCCUGUCCCCAGUGUGGCCGUGCUUACACGCUGGCCACCAAGCUGCGGCGCCACCUCAAAUCUCACUUGGAGGACAAGCCCUACCGCUGCCCCACCUGUGGCAUGGGCUACACCCUCCCGCAGAGCCUCAGGCGGCAUCAGCUCAGUCACCGGCCUGAGGCACCCUGCAGCCCACCCUCUGUGCCUUCUGCUGCUUCUGAGCCCACUGUGGUGCUCCUGCAGGCUGAGCCACAACUGCUGGACACACACAGAGAGGAGGAAGUCUCCCCCGCCAGGGAUGUUGUUGAGGUCACCAUUUCAGAAAGCCAGGAGAAGUGCUUUGUGGUGCCAGAGGAGCCAGAUGCCGCCCCCAGCCUGGUGCUAAUCCAUAAGGACAUGGGCCUCGGCGCCUGGGCAGAGGUGGUGGAGGUGGAGAUGGGCACCUGACAGCUUUGCCUUUUGCUGACACAGCUCCAUAAAGACUCGUGCUUUCUCA